CUCCUCCUGCGCGCCCCUCCGCGCGGCCCUCGCAGGGAGUGGGGCUCGGGUGCGCCGGCAGGGCCGCGCGGCGGCAGCAGGCGGGGGCGCGUGGCGCGGGCCGCGCUCGGGGAGGCGCCUGGGCCCGCCCUCCUCCGGGGCGCCGCGGGAGGGGCCCGGGUUGGCGCGGGGCGGGGAGAGCCGCCUGGCCCCUCCCCUCCGCCGCCCUCCCCAAAGUUGCCGUCUCCCCCGGGGCCGGCCGGUCUUAUGAUCCGGCGGAUCCUCCUGGGGAGGCCGGGCCGGGGAGAGGGCGCGGGCGCCGAGUGGCGGGGGCAGCGGGCGGGCGCGGCGACCGGGGCCGGGGCGGGGAUCCGGGCGGCGACCGCGGCGGCGGCAGCGCCCCGGGCCCGCCGCCCCCUCCCCUCCUGCGAGGGGAGCCGCUGCAUGGGGCCGGGGGGGCGGCCCUGCGGCGCGGAGCGGCGGCGACGGCGGCGGACCCCCCAGGCGGGCUGGGGCUGAGCCCGGGGCCGGGGCGGGGGCUCCGGGGGGACCAUGCCCGGAGGCCGGCCGGCAGCAGCAUGGCUCACGGGCCCGGCGCGCUGAUGCUCAAGUGCGUGGUGGUCGGCGACGGGGCGGUGGGCAAGACGUGCCUACUCAUGAGCUAUGCCAACGACGCCUUCCCGGAGGAGUACGUGCCCACCGUCUUCGACCACUACGCAGUCAGCGUCACCGUGGGGGGCAAGCAGUACCUCCUAGGACUCUAUGACACGGCCGGACAGGAAGACUAUGACCGUCUGAGGCCUUUAUCUUACCCAAUGACCGAUGUCUUCCUUAUAUGCUUCUCGGUGGUAAAUCCAGCCUCAUUUCAAAAUGUGAAAGAGGAGUGGGUACCGGAACUUAAGGAAUACGCACCAAAUGUACCCUUUUUAUUAAUAGGAACUCAGAUUGAUCUCCGAGAUGACCCCAAAACUUUAGCAAGACUGAAUGAUAUGAAAGAAAAACCUAUAUGUGUGGAACAAGGACAGAAACUAGCAAAAGAGAUGUCAGCACAUGUGGACGCCACACAGCAGGGACUCUGCUCUUUCGUUCAGUUCACUGACAUAUCCCCAGGACCUAAACAGUGCUUGACAUAUAGUAGAUACCCAGUAAAUAUGUGAUAGGAGCAUGCUGCUAUGUGGAAUGUUCAGCUUUAACCCAGAAGGGAUUGAAGACUGUUUUUGAUGAGGCUAUCAUAGCCAUUUUAACUCCAAAGAAACACACUGUAAAAAAAAGAAUAGGAUCAAGAUGUAUAAACUGUUGUUUAAUUACGUGAGAAACAUCUUCAGUGGCCAAGGAAACUGUCCAUUUCUCUCAGAAAGCAAAUGAAAUGCUACAGCUAUACCCAGACCUUUUAUAGGUAAUGAAGCAGUUCAAAACUUGAAAGAAAACAAAACCUGUCCUCAGAAUUCUAUAAAGUGUAUUAAGAAUGUUCCUUAAAGGUUUAAGAAGCAGUAAGCAGCAUCUGAAGCCACAAUCUAUUAUAAAUACUUUAUUUCAACUAGAAGGUACAAUCUCUCAGGGGUUUCAUAGUUUAAAAAGCUACAAUCACAUCAUGUUGUAACUACGUAAAAAACAGAGCUGUAAAUGGAACUGCUUGGCUUUGACCAUACACAUUUCUGCCCAGCCCUUACAGAAUCUGCACAAAGAAAUAUCUCCCUUUGCUCCAGUUAAUUGUUCUUGUAUGUAAGUUGCUUUCUAUUCCAGUAUAUCCAGAGUGGUGAAAUAACAAGGCCAGCCACGUAGCCAAAGGUCGCUCCAAGCGUACAGGAGAUGGGCCAUACCUGAGGAGAGAAUGUAUGAGAUCAAAAAAGAACAAAUGUUUUAUUAUUACUUGAGCACAAGUGUAACCUAAAUAUUUCUAUAUUAAAGCUUAAUGUGCUUUCUUAAAGAAUGCCAAAAGUGUAAUAAGGUCAUAACUGCAUUUAUCAUGAACACUAAAAAUGUACACAUUUUAGUUAAUGUGCAUUAAACUGUAACAAGGCUUCUGGCAAUUGUAGAUUUAGUUUGACGCUCCCCAAAGUGCAUGAGACACAUGCUAAAAUUACAAAUUAAAAUUUUGGGUCAGACUUUGCCAUAAUGAUAGACUCAAUUUAGCUCUCUGAACUAGUUGGUAAUUUUUUUUUUUUAAUUCCCACUUUGGCUGUGUACAUCAAAUGAAAUGAGAAGUGUGUAUGCUGACCAAACCACAAGAAACUUUCUUUAAGUUGUGUUAAAGAGGAAAGACCUAGAAUCCAAGCGUGUUACAUGAAAAUUGUAACAGAGCAGCUGCUUCCACCUUUCAGAUAUAGAUGUUGGAACCACAGCAGAAGUUAUAGAGCGACAACUUAUAUACACACCUAGAAUGUAAGUUAAACAAAAUACCGGCUUCCAGAGACCCCUUUUCUCCAGCCAUAUUACAUCAGGCUAGAAGUAAUUAAUGUUGAUUUAUUUCAUCUACAAGCAGUUGGUCCCUAAGUGAAAGGCUCUGCUUGAAAAAAAAAAGAAAAAAAAGUUGGAGGAAAAUUUUCAUGUUCUUCUGUGAAGCUUAUUUGGUACACUGGAGCCAUUUCUAAUCUUUCUCUGGGGGGAACAGGCCACAGAACUGUGUUAGAGGUGAACCAUCUUAAUUACUAGUUCUAUUACCUAAUUCAGCUUCCUUGUUUGGUCUGCUGUGGAUCUGCCUUAUUGCAUAUGCCAUGCAUCAGAUAAUGGAUGCAUCAGAUAAUGGUGUUAGACAAAGCUUCAUUGUGAACAACCUAAUGCAUUUUAGAGAAACAAUCUCAUCACAUUUUUUCUAGCCUUUCCUACAUUUAAACUUGCUGUUGCCCAAAUUAUAAUUUUUUAAAUGUCUUUGGUGGGCUUCUGUUAAUUCACAUGACUUGAGCUUAUAGCUAUGUCUACUGCACAGAUUGGGUAAUGGAACACUAAACUUUUAUACUUGAAAAUGACAGCCUUAAAUGCUCAUAUCAGUCACAAAUCUAGGAUGUACUGUCUUGUUGUAUGUGAGCUUUGUAGAGAUUUUUAAAAAUAUAAGCAUCACCUUCCCAUUGAAGAGUGGAGAGAGUCUACUGGAUGACUGGCCAGGAACUUUCUCUCUGAAUCGGACAUUUGGAUGUCUUCUUUCUUCCAAGAAAUGGUGGUUCACAUUAAAGUAUCAUGGCCUUAUGUAUGCUCAAAUGGAAUCUUAUGUAACUUUCUUAUUUAAUUUUGGUCUGCUUAUUUUUAGAUAAAAUUGAAAGGAAUUGUAUAAAUCAAUUAACAUAUUAGCUGAGUUGUCCAACACAUGGUAUAAACGAAUUACAACAGUAAACUAUUACACAUUUCCAACUUGCCUUUGGGGAUUUAUGAGGAUUUUUUUUGGUGGGGGGAGGGGGCUCCAAUUCAUAUCUCUGAAACCCUUCACACUUGGUUUACUAAUUCAAAGUUAGAAGUCUAGAAUUUGCCCUGCCCUAACAGAAACAGAUUAGGAAUUUGUCUACACAAACUGGUGUCACCUGUUUCUUGACUGGGAUUUGGUUUCCUCAUUAUAAAUAUGGGAGGUAGAACAGAGAUCUCCAACGUCUCUCCCAUUUAUCACAGUAAUUUUCUUAUUCACAGUAAUCAUUGUUGGAUGUUACCUUUUCAGCUUCACAUUCUCAAGAUGGUAAAAAUCAUGUAUAUAGAUUAUCAGAACUCUAAGCAAAGAUGACUGUCACAUCUGAAGCUGAGGUGCCUUAGGUACUCUACUGACCUUGAUGGGUUUGGAGUUCCCCAUUGCUUAUCAAGAGCUUUUUAAUUGCUUUGGUUCUUUAGUUUUUCUUUUUGCAAAAAUCCUUCCUGUCACUUUAACUAAAAACCAAAGAUUUGUUUUCUAUUGAUAAGCAGACUAGAGAAAAACUGCCUUAUUUUCAGAAGCAUGUCUUCAUUCAAAGCUUAGGCUUCAAUAGAAAUUCAGACUAAUCACUGAAAUGACUAUUUCAAACUAGUGAAAUAUCUGGGAAAUAAACUGCUUCAAAAAUAUUUUACUGACAUGAAUUUUGCUAGUGAAUACAAAUACACUGCCUCAAAUAAGGCCAUGUAUGAAUGAACUUACAAGAUAUUUGAGUUAAUCAGUGUUUGCAUAUAGAGAAUUAGUUCUAAAGUUCUUAAAAAUAAAUUUAGGGGCUCCCUGAAAUUUUAUUUAAUACUUUGCUAACUUACACUCUUGUUUUAUCUCCACAGGUACAUUUUAGGUUAGCUCAUGGUGAAUUCUAUUUACAAUAAGUGGAGCUUGGAUUAAUGGGUUUUGUUAUGAAUUAUCUUAGUGACUUUAGACACUGUUUCCAUUUGAUUUUUAACUAUUUAAAAUACCAAAUUAAAUACCAGUUUGUUGGUUGUUACUUUUAAAUGAUUGUUACUUUAACAGUGUCCCUUCUUAACACAUGGGGUUACAAAUAAAAUACUAUGCAUAGUUUACUAUCUACGUAAAGCACUGAACUUUUUACCUUAGUAGUUUUUAUUUAUUACCCUAUGUAAACAUUUAGGAUAAUACUCUUUCCUCUAUUUAUGCUGAGAGUCUACUAAUCAUUGGCAAAGUAUGAGUCCCUAUACUCUGUUAAAAAAAGCUCACUGUUAAAGUAUAGGGAGAAUAGUAAUCCCUCAUGAAUCCCAGCUAGAUUCCAAUUUGGGUUACUAAAUUGUAUUUUAAUCAUUUUGUAAUUUCAGUAUGGCUCUUUGUUCUCAAACACAUACAUACCACCACGCACAUUCUUUUAAACAGCUGCCACACCUCACCUCCAACAGAAUGCCAAAAAUGAAAUGUUAAAAAAUUUUGUCUAAUGAAGGGUUACGGCUUGGAACACUUGGUUAUUCAUGUUAUGUAAAUCAAGAAGUGCAUGCCAUCAGCAAAUUAAAAUGUGGACUGGCUUUGAAGACUGUUAA